AGUGCUCUGUGGGAUACUGGAAGUCUCGAGCGUCGGCUCCGGGUUCCCAGCCCUCCUCUGGCCCGCACUCAUAGAAACAUUCACACACCCCCUGCCUCCCCUCUCUUCCCUCUCCGCCUCCCCCUUCCCCCCCUCGCGAUAAGAAGACCCGGCGGCAGGAGAGGGGAUGAAGAUGGCGGACGCGAAGCAGAAGCGGAACGAGCAGCUGAAACGCUGGAUCGGCUCCGAGACGGACCUCGAGCCUCCGGUGGUGAAGCGCCAGAAGACCAAGGUGAAGUUCGACGAUGGCGCCGUCUUCCUGGCUGCUUGCUCCAGCGGCGACACGGACGAGGUCCUCAAGCUGCUGCACCGCGGCGCCGACAUCAAUUACGCCAAUGUGGACGGACUCACUGCCCUGCACCAGGCUUGCAUUGAUGACAAUGUUGAUAUGGUGAAGUUUCUGGUAGAAAAUGGAGCAAAUAUUAAUCAACCUGAUAAUGAAGGCUGGAUACCACUACAUGCAGCAGCUUCCUGUGGAUAUCUUGAUAUUGCAGAGUUUUUGAUUGGUCAAGGAGCACAUGUAGGGGCUGUCAACAGUGAAGGAGAUACACCUUUAGAUAUUGCGGAGGAGGAGGCAAUGGAAGAGCUACUUCAAAAUGAAGUUAAUCGGCAAGGGGUUGAUAUAGAAGCAGCUCGAAAGGAAGAAGAACGGAUCAUGCUUAGAGAUGCCAGGCAGUGGCUAAAUAGUGGUCAUAUAAAUGAUGUCCGGCAUGCAAAAUCUGGAGGUACAGCACUUCACGUUGCAGCUGCUAAAGGCUAUACGGAAGUUUUAAAACUUUUAAUACAGGCAGGCUAUGAUGUUAAUAUUAAAGACUAUGAUGGCUGGACACCUCUUCAUGCUGCAGCUCAUUGGGGUAAAGAAGAAGCAUGUCGAAUUUUAGUGGACAAUCUGUGUGAUAUGGAGAUGGUCAACAAAGUGGGCCAAACAGCCUUUGAUGUAGCAGAUGAAGACAUUUUAGGAUAUUUAGAAGAGUUGCAAAAGAAACAAAAUCUGCUCCAUAGUGAAAAACGGGACAAGAAAUCUCCACUAAUUGAAUCAACAGCAAAUAUGGACAAUAAUCAGUCACAGAAGACCUUUAAAAACAAAGAGACGUUGAUUAUUGAACCAGAGAAAAAUGCAUCCCGUAUUGAAUCUCUGGAACAAGAAAAGGUUGAUGAAGAAGAAGAAGGAAAGAAGGAUGAGUCUAGCUGCUCUAGUGAAGAAGAUGAGGAAGAUGACUCGGAAUCAGAAGCUGAAACAGAUAAGACAAAACCCCUGGCUUCUGUAACUAAUGCCAACACUUCUAGUACACAAGCAGCUCCUGUAGCUGUUACAACACCUACUGUGUCAUCAGGUCAAGCAACACCUACAUCACCUAUUAAAAAGUUUCCAACCACAGCUACAAAAAUUUCUCCCAAAGAAGAAGAGAGAAAAGAUGAGUCUCCUGCAACUUGGAGGUUAGGACUUAGAAAGACGGGCAGCUAUGGUGCACUUGCUGAAAUCACAGCAUCUAAAGAGGGUCAGAAAGAAAAAGAUACUGCAGGUGUUACACGUUCAGCUUCAAGUCCCAGACUUUCCUCCUCUUUGGAUAAUAAAGAAAAGGAGAAAGAUAGUAAAGGAACUAGGCUUGCAUAUGUUGCACCUACAAUACCAAGACGACUAGCCAGUACAUCUGACAUUGAAGAGAAAGAAAACAGAGAUUCUUCAAGUUUGCGAACAAGUAGUUCAUAUACAAGGAGAAAAUGGGAAGAUGAUCUUAAAAAAAAUAGCUCAGUUAAUGAAGGAUCAACGUAUCAUAAAAGUUGCUCCUUUGGUAGAAGACAAGAUGAUUUGAUUAGUUCUAGUGUUCCAAGCACCACAUCAACACCAACAGUUACCUCUGCAGCUGGGCUUCAGAAAAGCCUGCUUUCCAGCACAAGCACUACUACAAAGAUUACAACGGGUUCUUCCUCAGCAGGCACACAAAGCAGUACCUCAAAUCGUUUGUGGGCUGAGGAUAGUACUGAGAAAGAAAAGGACAGUGUUCCUACGGCAGUGACCAUUCCUGUUGCUCCAACUGUUGUAAAUGCUGCAGCUUCUACCACAACCCUGACUACAACUACUGCUGGCACUGUCUCCUCCACAACAGAGGUCAGGGAGAGACGCAGAUCAUACCUCACUCCUGUUAGGGAUGAAGAGUCUGAAUCCCAAAGAAAAGCAAGAUCUAGACAAGCAAGACAAUCUAGAAGAUCAACACAGGGAGUGACAUUAACUGAUCUUCAAGAAGCUGAGAAAACAAUAGGAAGAAGUCGUUCUACCCGAACCAGAGAACAAGAAAAUGAAGAAAAAGAAAAAGAGGAAAAAGAGAAACAAGAUAAAGAGAAACAAGAAGAAAAGAAGGAGUCAGAAACAUCUAGAGAAGAUGAAUAUAAACAAAAGUACUCCAGAACGUAUGAUGAGACUUACCAGCGUUAUAGGCCAGUAUCAACUUCAAGUUCAACCACUCCAUCCUCUUCACUUUCUACUAUGAGCAGUUCACUGUAUGCUUCAAGUCAACUAAACAGGCCAAAUAGUCUUGUAGGCAUAACUUCUGCUUACUCCAGAGGAAUAACAAAAGAAAAUGAAAGAGAGGGAGAAAAAAGAGAAGAGGAGAAAGAAGGAGAAGAUAAAUCACAACCUAAAUCAAUCAGAGAACGACGACGACCAAGAGAGAAAAGAAGAUCUACAGGAGUUUCAUUUUGGACACAAGAUAGUGAUGAAAAUGAACAAGAACAACAAUCAGACACAGAAGAGGGAUCCAAUAAGAAAGAAACUCAGACGGAUUCCAUUUCUAGAUAUGAAACCAGUUCUACAUCAGCUGGUGAUCGAUAUGAUUCCUUGCUGGGUCGCUCUGGAUCAUACAGUUACUUAGAAGAAAGAAAACCUUACAGCAGCAGGCUAGAAAAGGAUGACUCAACUGACUUUAAAAAGCUUUAUGAACAAAUUCUAGCUGAAAAUGAAAAGCUGAAGGCACAGCUACAUGAUACAAAUAUGGAACUAACAGAUCUUAAAUUACAGUUGGAAAAGGCCACCCAGAGACAAGAAAGAUUUGCUGAUAGAUCACUGUUGGAAAUGGAAAAAAGGGAACGAAGAGCUCUAGAAAGAAGAAUAUCUGAAAUGGAAGAAGAGCUCAAAAUGUUACCAGACCUAAAAGCAGACAACCAGAGGCUAAAGGAUGAAAAUGGGGCCUUGAUCAGAGUUAUAAGCAAACUUUCCAAAUAAAAAAAAAAAAAGCAGCAAGUAAUGGAAUUGCACAUAUUAGUAACCCAGUGGACCAUAAUUGGCAGUCACUGGAAGUCUGGGAAGAAUCCUUGGAGACUGUCAUUUUCGGAUAUCCUGCCAAAUGCCCUCUUAUCUAGAAUUUUUGUUUCAUUUUGUUUAAUUUUCUGGGGUGUUUUUGUUGUUGUUGGUUUGUUUUUUGUUUUUUUUUUUUAAUCAAGACCAUUGUUUCAUGUUAAUGCAGCUGCUGAGAAGAUUUUUUUUUAAUGACUGAGAAAACUUGUUUACAGCUCCAGCAUAUAAGGAAAGUGUUCAAGGCCAGAUAUGCCUCAGAUAUUUAACCAGUAAGCCUUAGUUGUACAUAAAUACUUUUGUGUCAACAAAAACUUUCAGCUCUCACAGAAGACAGUUACUCAACAUUUUUUGAUGUGCCACAGUUUCGAGUUUUUCGAUAUUUAAAUUUUUUGGCUUUUCAUCUAAGUUUGGGUUUGUAUUUUUUCCUUCUAAACUCUUCAUGUGGCAGAGUCUUCUAUGUUUUCACAGCUUUUUCAUUACAGAAAAGAACACUUGCUCUUCUGUGAUUAUUGUCAUGUAUUAGGCUAAUGCUGUGUUGUCUCCCACCUGGAACUGAAUUGCUUGGUGGAACAUAUGCUUUCACUGUUUGUGCAAUAUGCAUUUAUUUCUUAUAUGAAUGCUUUAAAGUCAUUUGAGGUUAGAUCUUUUAAUUCCUAUUUUCUGCUUCAUUGGUCACUUUUUUUUUAUUGUAGUAUAAGAUGUUAGAUUCUGUAAUCUUCACAUUCAUUUUAGCAGGUACUGAGUGAUGCUGUAUAUACAAAUAAGUGUAUUGUUUUGAUUUUUAGACCACCACAUGGCAUGCUUGACUAUUUCUUAUUUCAAAUGUCUGCUAAUGCAGAGUAGGCUACUCCAUGAUAGUGUUAAAAAACAAAAUUUGCUAACAAUGUGAUAUAAAGACUUUAAAAGUUACACAUUAUGUGGAGCCCUAUCUUUACAAAAGUUUCCUACUGUAAAGUGCUUUUAUUUUCAGUUUUCACUUGAUAGUACUCAACCAUAAUUAAAGUUGCAUAAGAUAAUUGCUUUACAUUUCACAUACCUAUAUUUAUCUGAGUGCUGUCUAAAACUGUUGUGCUAGCCAAAGUAAUGCUAUGAAAUCAUUUGCAGAAUUAACCCGUGAGUUAAUGUUAAAUGCACUGUUAUUGCCAUGUGAAGAGGCAUCGACUUUGAUACCACCAUCAUGUUCAGACCAUUUUAUACAUUUCAGUGGCCUUUUUUUUUUUUUAAGGAAAAAAAAGCGCAAAACCAAGUACAUAGUGACGAUGGCUUUUAUUUGGACAAAUAGCUUUUAUAUUUUCAUUAAACCAUGCAAAAAAUACUACAUCUUUCUGGCACAUAACUGUCUCCUUAACCACUGAACAGUUCAGCCAUUUGAAUAAAUUGUACAUUGUAAAGCUUAUAGUAGCUGAUUGUAUUAUUGAUUGUAUUGUAUACUAUAUUAAAUGUGAAUUUGUACCCCUUCAUUUUAAAAGGUCAUUGUGUUCUACUGCCUAUUUUAGAUUACUUUGGGGUUGGGGAAGGGUGUUUUGGUAAGCAGGAUUUUAAGUCCUCUCUCUCUCGAUUGGUUUUAUGAAGAUAUAAGGUUAUGCUCUUACUACCAAGCUCAGGAUUCUUGAUUUUAAAGGUACAAGGAUAGUUGUGGGAGUUUUAUUUUUGGUUAUAUUUGAACUGUAUGAAUGGUAGGUCUGAAUAUUGAGAAUUUCCAUGGUCUUAUGUGGAGGUAAAAUAUACAGAUAACUGAUCAGUUUGAGUGACUGCAACAUGUUCUGGUUGCACAACAGUUAGGCAUGCUAUGGUUUAUAUUUGUGAAGUUUGGAUGCCUGUGAAGAAUGAUUAAAUACAUGUUUCUAAUAUUUUAGUGUUUUGUAUUUAGGUUAUUUAUUCUUUGUAUCUAAAACUGAACAGCUACUGUGCUAUAUUGAUUUUAUUGGUAGUAUUGAGCAGACCUUGUUUCUGCAUGAAACUAGUUGCAAAACCCACUAUUUUGGAAAUAAAAAUGUAUUUUGACAUAUACAAAUAAAAUGAAUAAAACUAUUUUAAAUGUGUGAACUUUUAAUGAAGACAUUUUAAAUUUUGUUCUGAGAUAUUUAAAUUCUGCAUGGGUAUUUUUUCACUAAUUGCUUUACUUGGAUACCAAUUUGAAUAAUUUCUGAAAUUGUAAUAUUGUGAUAAUUUGCACAGCAUUGUACAUGCACAUCUGUAAAUGCAAUCUUAAUUGCCAUAUUUAUGCAAUCUGUGUACCAAUUUGGACAAAUGUUUAUAUAUUUUACAUAAAGCUGUCUGUAUGCAGAA